GUUGCCAUGGUGAUCGCCGCCGCUGGCUCAGGCGGACCAGGCCGCGCGGAGCCCCAGCUUUCACAGCCAUCGCUGGUGAGUCAGCUCGCCCACUCUGUCCGACCCUCCCGGUCACCCAACCCCGUGCUGGCACAUCCCGAGGCCAGGGCCGCGAGGGCACAGCGUCCGCGCCCACUUCCCGCCCCUAUAACUUGAAAGCGGCCUGCGGCCCCGGGGCGUCCUCAUUUCCGGAGCGCAAACUCUGGGCCAGGCCCGCGCUGGUUGUGGAGGAGAGCCAGGUCAGAUGCGGGAAGACAACCGGACUCCGCCAGGACCACCCCAGCCCAGCCUGGAGAGGAGUCCGGACAGAAAAAGGAGACAGAGGGGCUGUUGAGGAGGCUCGAGGAGUCAGAGGCCUGGUGAAGUGAGGGUUUUCAGGGAAAAGGCCUAGUUGGCUGAAAGUUAAGGCCCCCAGGCCCACCUAGAGCCUUCGUCCUUUGCAGACUGGGAGCAGGAGACCCCUCCCCACUCUACUUCCACUGCCUGAGCUGUGCCAUGCCUCACAGCCCAGUAAGUGGUACACGCCGGAAGCCUGUUUGCAGCUCAGGGAGCACUUCCACGGGCAGGUCAGCGCUGCCUGCCAACGCAGGAACACGGGGACUGUCGGGCUCAAACUCUCCAAGGUGGUGGUGGUUGGCGAUCUCUACGUGGGGAAGACCAGCCUCAUCCACAGGUUUUGCAAGAAUGUUUUUGAUCGAGACUACAAGGCCACCAUUGGGGUGGACUUUGAAAUUGAGCGCUUUGAGAUUGCUGGGAUUCCCUAUAGCCUCCAGAUUGAUCAUCACGGCCUUUGACCUCACUGACGUGCAGACCCUGGAGCAUACCAGGCAGUGGUUGGAGGAUGCUCUGAGGGAGAACGAGGCAGGCUCCUGCUUCAUCUUCCUCGUGGGAACCAAGAAGGACCUUCUGUCAGGGGCCGCAUGUGAGCAGGCCGAAGCAGACGCUGUGCACCUGGCCAGGGAGAUGCAGGCCGAGUACUGGCGAGAACGUGAAGGCAUUCUUCAGCCGCGUAGCCGCCCUGGCAUUCGAGCAGUCGGUGCUGCAGGACCUGGAGAGGCAGAGCAGUGCCCGGCUCCAGGUCGGCAAUGGAGACCUAAUCCAAAUGGAAGGGAGUCCGCCCGAGACCCAGGAGAGCAAGAGGCCCUCCAGCCUGGGCUGCUGCUAACUGGGGCCUGCGUGGAAGGCCUCCGCUCCCUGCACACACACGGACAGGAAUUUCCGUGACUGUGGUGUGGAGACUGGAGCCCAAGCUCUGCAGCGUGUCGCCCUCAAGCUGUAGGCCCAUGUUCCAGUCCCUCCACCCACCCACCGGGCUCAGCUCCAGGGCACAGUCACUUGUCCGUUGCAGGUUGGGCACUAGAAAAGGCCCCCACUGGCUGCCUGGGAGCCCCACACCACCGGGCCAGUGCAGGCACUGUGGUGAUCCCAUAAAAGGCCAGUCCAUUUGCAGGGUCAUCAGACAGUCACCUUUGGCCUCAAGAGGCCUCAGAACUGCAAACUCCUGCGUCGGUCUAUACUACUCGGCCAUGGCCCACAUCAGCAGUCAACCCUGCACUCUUUCCCAGCGAUCUUGGAUGUGUCCCCAGGAUCCGUCACAGUGUUCCAGGCAACCUGGACUUGUCAAAGUCAGCACCUGAAGGAGAGGCCACCUGCCAUUCCCCCUGGGAGUUUUCUGUUGUCAGCAGGACUUAUGGUUCUGGGUCUCAGAGCUUCAGGCCUCACUGUCCUUCUGCCACGGAUGCUCAAGGUUCCUGGGCAGACCAGCACCUCUGGAGGACAAUGGACAAAAUGUCUCUUAGACCUGUUCUGGCUGAAGGGCUAUCUCUGGCACCUCUGAGAUCCCUAGGUCCUGCCCUCCUGGUCCGUGGGCCAGGAUGUGCAGAACAACCACUCAGGCCUUUCUGGCCCACCUGGACAGUGCAUUUACCUGUGUGCUGCGGGAGGCAGACUGCACAGCUGUCCUAGGGUAACUCACUCUGCAGCCCUUGAACAUGGCACUGCCCUCCUCUGGCACUCAUGCUGGGCCUGUGCCCACUGCUGCCUCUCCAUCCCUCUCUCAUUGGCCUAUACAUCUCUUAGGACCUUUGUAAUGGUGUCCAUGCACCUUUAGAGGACUUCAGAGGCCCUGCCAAGUCUAGCAUGUUCCUGUCUCCAACACCGCCUCCUGCACAUGCAGAGCAGACAGAAAUACCCCACACAUUCCCCAGCCUCUCUGCCCAGUAUGCUCAUCCACAGGGUUUUCUCACUGCUAUGAACCAGCCCCACAGCCCCAGGCCCCUGUCACCUGGCUAUGCCCACUCAUCCCACCCGUCUCGUGCUGUUGCUUCCCGUAGAUGGCGAGCACCUUGCAGGCAGCCUUCUGAUCAGUACUGCUCUCCUAGGGCCUGGCACACUGCAGCUGCCCUGUAAAUGUUCAGCUCAGCGAUUGCCAAAUACCAGUUAGGGAAGAACACUGGCAUCUUUUUCUAUUCAUUCCCCCUUCAACAUAUUUUUUGUAGUUUUUUAUAUAAAUGACUUUUUUUUUUUUUUGAGAUGGAGUUUCACCCUUGUUGCCCAGGCUGGAGUGCAAUGGCGUAAUCUCGGCUCAGUGCAACCUCUGCCUCCCAGGUUGAAGCGAUUCUCCUGCCUCAGCCUCCCAAGUAGCUGGGAUUACAGGCAUGCACCACCAUGCCUGGCUAAUUUUGUAUUUUUAGUAGAGAUGGGGUUUCUCCAUGUUGGUCAGGCUGCUCUCGGACUCCUGAUCUCAGGUGACCUGCCCACCUCGGCCUCCCGAAGUGCUGGGAUUACAAGGGUGAGCCACCAUGCCCGGCCAUAAAUGAUUUUAUUCAUUUUUAUGUUUUCUUUUGGGCGGCGGGAUGGAGUCUCUGUCACCCAGGCUGGCGUGCAAUGGCACGAUCUUGGCUCACUGCAAGCUUCCCCUUCCGGGUUCAUGCCAUUCUCCUGCCUCAGCCUCCCGAGUAGCUGGGACUACAGGCACGUGUGACCAUGCCGGGCUAAUUUUUUAUAUUUUUAGUAGAGAGAGGUUUCACCGUGUUAGCCAGGAUGGUCUCGAUGAUCUGACCUCGUGAUCUGCCCGCCUCGGCCUCCCAAAGUGCUGGGAUUACAGGCCUGAGCCACCGCGUCCGGCCUCCAUAAAUGACUUUUAAAGGGGUUGUAUGUUUAGUGUGAACAAAGACAGUACAAAGCAUAUAAAAUACAAGGUGAAAGCCCCCCCCCCGCCACAUUAGCUGCGCCCCUGAAGUGUCUCCAGCAGAAGAGAUGGAUGAAUGGAAGGACACACAGAUGGACAGAGAGCAGGAAAGACUGUUAGCUCUGCUAACAGUCAGGACUAUUCCUUCUGGACUCUGUGCCUUUGCCUGCACAGCUAGUGUUGAUGGCUUGUUUGUUGUUUUCACCAGAGUGAGCUCCUUCUGGACAUACUGCCUGGCAGCCUGCCUUCCUAGGGAGCUGGCGCCAAGGCCUCUCCCUGAUGGCACACAAGGAGCCUCCUUCCUGUAGCAGCGCCCAGUUUUCAUGUGGAUGGAUUGUAGUUCAUUUGACCCUCCCCAUCCGCGGGCCAUCCGGCUUGUGUCCAGCUUUUAGCUCUUGCCAAUGGUGCUGCAGUGGCCAUUCUUGUAGUUAUAGCUUUGCGUACUCAGGAAGGCCCUUCUCCCGACUGCGGCCCCCAGCCUGGUCCACUAAAUGCAGCCUGUGGUCGGGCAGACAGCAUUGGGGUCCAUUAGGAAGACCAGGUUUGCUGGGCAUAAGCUUCACAGGACGGGAGAACCUGCCCAUGGUGGACUGUCGUUCUCCACAGCUCCCUUCCCUUGCCCCUUCGGGCCUCCAGGAUAUGUUUGCGGGGGUGGGUGUGGUGUCCAGCUGUUACCAGCUUCUGAGCUAGAGCUGUACUGCCUCACGUACACCCCCACCUCUGUAAAUGGUCCUUGAUUAAAUCGUCCUCAUAUUACCUCCUGCAAUGUGCCAGCUGAUUCCCACACACCCUGACUGACAUAGUUGUGGCCUCUCGAACUUUGAUAUUUGGCCUGGGAGGACAGAAGAGUAAGGUCGCCACGGAAACGCAAGGGGCUCAGUUGUCCCCCCACCCCAAGUUGAUGCAGCAUCUUCUCGGUCAGAAUUGCUUCAGGGUGGUUUGCGCACCCUCACUUUGAUGAUUUAAUGAAGACAUUUCCUUCUUUCCCAGCAUCGGGCAGUAAGUUUCCUGGGCAGAGGCACUUUCUGUUGGUCUGGUCUUGUGGGCCCAGGCAAGCAGCCCCCUGCAGCCAAGGUGCGGCAAUGACCACAGUGACCGCGUCCAAGUGCUGCCGAAACGCCUUUUUCCUCUUCCCUGUUUCCCUGGACCCUUUCCUGCUCUCUGUCCAUCUGUGUGUCCUUCCGUUCACCUGUCUCUUCUGCUGGAGACACGUACCUGAAGCAGGUCCUCUCCUGUCACUUCCUGGCUCCCCAGGGCUAGGUCCCAGGGUGCUCUCGCUCUGGCUUUCGAGGCUCCUCACCACCCAGCCCACCCCACCCCCACAGGCCCCUGUGCUCCAGUUUCAUCCCUGGUCACAAUGCAGUCUGCAGAUGCCAGACCCCUCUUCUGUGCCCAACGGCUGGGACACCCCUACUCCCAGAGAGGCCUCUGUGGACACCCCCACAGCUCUCGCAGCACUUGAUACCUUGAGUGUGAUUGGUCACAUCUGGGCUUUCUCCCCCACCCAUCUGUGGAACCCCAAGAGCCAGGACAGUGACCUCAUCACCUCUACUGUCUCCCCUAGCACCUCUGGGAGGAAGGGCCCACAGUAGGUGCUCAAUAGAUGUGUAAAGAAGGCAGGGAAGCAAGAAGGUUGCUCAAACAAGACCAUGUUCCCAGCAGACAGAUUGCACUCUGACCCAGAUGCCACCACACGAAACUUACACCUGCCUGGGGAACAAUCCUGUGCUUGGCUCUCCUUGGUGGCCAGGGACAGUUGUGCCUCAUCCCUCACUUGCAAACCCCAGUCCUGUCUGACCCAGAGACCCUCACAGGGCAUCAGCCAGUGAAGGCGGUUUGGGGCUGGAGGAUAUGUUCUGAUCUUGGGAAGAGCUUGGUAGGAGCCAGCCACAGAAAGUUUCAGGGCAGAACUGAACAGGUCUCGGGAAGGACACUUCAUGCCAGCUAGAGAGGCUCUGGGCACAGGAAAGAAUUGGACUUCGGGCAGAAAAAUGUUUGUGCUAUUUAGUACUAUGUAACAAAUCACUCCAAAACUUCAUUGCUUAAAGCAACAAGCAUGUAUUAUUUCUCAUGA